GAAGCUCUGUUUGGUGCUUUGGAUCCAUUUCCAUCGGUCCUUACAGCCGCUCGUCAGACUCCAGCAGCCAAGAUGGUGAAGCAGAUCGAGAGCAAGACUGCUUUUCAGGAAGCCUUGGACGCUGCAGGUGAUAAACUUGUAGUAGUUGACUUCUCAGCCACGUGGUGUGGGCCUUGCAAAAUGAUCAAGCCUUUCUUUCAUUCCCUCUCUGAAAAGUAUUCCAACGUGAUAUUCCUUGAAGUAGAUGUGGAUGACUGUCAGGAUGUUGCUUCAGAGUGUGAAGUCAAAUGCAUGCCAACAUUCCAGUUUUUUAAGAAGGGACAAAAGGUGGGUGAAUUUUCUGGAGCCAAUAAGGAAAAGCUUGAAGCCACCAUUAAUGAAUUAGUCUAAUCAUGUUUUCUGAAAAUAUAACCAGCCAUUGGCUAUUUAAAACUUGUAAUUUUUUUAAUUUACAAAAAUAUAAAAUAUGAAGACAUAAACCCAGUUGCCAUCUGCGUGACAAUAAAACAUUAAUGCUAACACUUUUUAAAACCGUCUCAUGUCUGAAUAGCUUUCAAAAUAAAUGUGAAAUGGUCAUUUAAUGUAUUUUCCUAUAUUCUCAAUCACUUUUUAGUAACCUUGUAGGCCACUGAUUAUUUUAAGAUUUUAAAAAUUAUUAUUGCUACCUUAAUGUAUUGCUACAAAAAUCUCUUGUUGGGGGCAAUGCAGGUAAUAAAGUAGUAUGUUGUUAUUUGUUA